GCAAAGCUGCGCUGGCCGCUCGCGGAGGGAGAGGCUGCAGAGCGAGGGCAGGAGACAAAUGACCGGGAGCCAUGACGUCAUCGGGGGCGCAGGAAAGCAGGUGCUCUGCUGCUUUUGCAAGCAGAGAAAUAAGAGUUUGGGCACCUACCCAGGGGUCCCAGGGAAUGCCCUGUGGCUCCUGACCUCCCCCGCCUGUAAUGCUCUGAGCACUUCAGCAGUAAUGCAUGGAAGAGAUAAGGGUCUGUGACCCAUGGAACUGUCCAAGUCCUCUCUGACACCCGCUUCUUUUCCUGCCGUGAAGGUAAGCCACUUUAUAGAUCCUAGGCCUGAAACCCAAUGUUGGGAGGGAGUGUUUGUUUUCAAGAAGAAAGAGAGACUGAAACUAGAACAUGCACAUUUCUAUCCAGAAGAAAACAGUUGGAGUAGACUAGAGUCCUACAAAGAGGGCAACAGGGAAGAAGAUUCUGGACUGAGUAAAGGGGACCCACUCCUGGGUCCACCUCCUGCCUGGGCCCUCUGGAGAGAGAAUUGGCCAGAUUCAGCCCUGAGUCACAGCACCCUCCCCAGUUGCUGCCUCACAGCCAUCUCCACACCAGCAGCCAUGCCCCCAGCGGCAGCUCGCCCACACCUCUGUGGGACCUCCCCACCGUCUCGCAGCCCAUCUGCUCCAGGCUUCUACUGACGAUUUCGUAUUUCACAUGGACUCAUUUCUCCUCAGACACUCCAGAUGGGGAAUGCCUUUCUGCAAUAUCAAAGUGCCCCAUUAGACUGGGGAGGAAUCAUGAGGGGACAUACCCCUGCCCCUGCCACAGAGUCGAGCAUGGCAGCUGAAUAUCUCUCACACUGGCAUGGCCCCCAUCCUCUGGAGAAAGGAGGCCUCAGUGCAGUCAGCCUCUUCAGGAGGCAGAAAUGUUGAGAAGUUCUCGCCACCCCUGCUGGGUGACUUUGGGGAGGUGUCUCCUCAGACCUCUGUUUCUCCAUCUGGACGGACUACUUCCAGCAACCCAGUCUCCUGCCAUGUCCGACCCCAUCACGCUGAACGUCGGGGGGAAGCUCUAUACAACCUCACUGGCGACCCUGACCAGCUUCCCUGACUCCAUGCUAGGCGCCAUGUUCAGCGGGAAGAUGCCCACCAAGAGGGACAGCCAGGGCAACUGCUUCAUUGACCGUGACGGCAAAGUGUUCCGCUAUAUCCUCAACUUCCUGCGGACCUCCCACCUUGACCUGCCUGAGGACUUCCAGGAGAUGGGGCUGCUCCGCAGGGAGGCCGACUUCUACCAGGUGCAGCCCCUGAUUGAGGCCCUGCAGGAGAAGGAAGUGGAGCUCUCCAAGGCCGAGAAGAAUGCCAUGCUCAACAUCACACUGAACCAGCGUGUGCAGACGGUCCACUUCACUGUGCGCGAGGCACCCCAGAUCUACAGCCUCUCCUCUUCCAGCAUGGAGGUCUUCAACGCCAACAUCUUCAGCACCUCCUGCCUCUUCCUCAAGCUCCUUGGCUCUAAGCUCUUCUACUGCUCCAAUGGCAAUCUCUCCUCCAUCACCAGCCACUUGCAGGACCCCAACCACCUGACUCUGGACUGGGUGGCCAAUGUGGAGGGCCUGCCAGAGGAGGAGUACACCAAGCAGAACCUCAAGAGGCUCUGGGUGGUGCCCGCCAACAAGCAGAUCAACAGCUUCCAGGUCUUCGUGGAAGAGGUACUGAAAAUCGCUCUGAGCGAUGGCUUCUGCAUCGAUUCUUCUCACCCACAUGCUCUGGAUUUUAUGAACAAUAAGAUUAUUCGAUUAAUACGGUACAGGUAAAAGGACCCCAACAACACUGGAGAUGGGGAGUCCCAGGAAGCUCAUGUCAGCCAGGUCUUGGAGGGCAUCUCGCCAGUGGUGCGAGGCAGGGGACUAUACUAAUCUGUAUUAAUUGUGUAGCAGGACUUGAUUCCCCCCAUGAUGAAGUCCACCUUUUGGAAUCCAGUGUCCUCUGAACAGAACCACCUUUUUUCUUGCCAUUUUGAGCUGCAGACAGGCGGUUUAUUAUGACAAGUGAAGAGUCAGCUGAUGUGUACUAAAGGAGGCCAUAGGAGGAUUUUCCAGCCAGGACAAAAGAGCAGCAGUUUUCUCCUGGGCUCCAUCUCUCUGUACCGCUAGCCAGUGCCGCAUUUAUCCAUCUGUAAGAAGGCCCUGGUGGAGAGGAUGGGAUGAGAACAAGAGGCUACCUCCAGUUAACCAGGACAUAAAGUCCCCAGCGGUUCCUGUCACACCUGCUCCUCCCUCCCCAGGGUGCAUCCAUGAUCGUGGAUGUUUGCCCAGGGGUGACCAUGUUUGGCUGGCUUGGAAUGCUGUGCAUUCUCAGAGCUCUGUUAGUGUCCCCUCUUGGGGGUCAGAGAUGAGGUGUGGCAGGGUCUAGAGGAAUGAGUGUCCAGGCAGAGUUCAGAAGGUAGGAAUGUCCCUCUUGAUAGGGCUGAAUCAAGGGAUUCCUGGCUUUAGAAAGGGUCUGCUAUCUUUGCAAAAAUGUGCAAGUAUCUGUAGCCAGUGUAAUGAAAUCACUUCCAAAUCCAGCCUGUUACCUGACUUUUGUCAUUGUUUUCCCAAAAAUUUGAGGUAUCAUUGAAACAGGUCAUUUUAAACAAAUCUAUUACGGAUUCUCAGGGUUGGAAAUAAUUCGAUGAUUGCUUAGUCCUCCCCCACCCCUAGAACACCCCAGCACAUCUGAAGAUGAGCGCCUCUCCCUGGGUACCUGCAAGUGAUCACCUUGGCCUGCUUGCAUACCUUGGCUGAUAGGAAGCGCGCCAUCCCCAAGGCAGCUCCUGCUGUGGUUGGACAGUGCUGACUGUUAGACAGUUCUUCCCUAUAUUGAGCCAAAAUCUGUCCUGCCACUUGCUGGAUCUUGGUUGCAGACCUUCCCAUUCACCCAGUUAUAUAUCUUUGCUUUCAAAAUAGUCACCUUGAGAGACCAGACAUUUUUCUGAAAACAUCAUUACUCAGAAUUCAGAUUCCCCUCUGGGAUCUGUCUUCAGAAUCAAAGUUAGCUCUUUUCUAUCCCCUGUAAGUCAGUCCCCUUUUGUUGUAGCUUCACCUCGUUUGUGACCCCCACUUCACCCACCUUCCCCACCAUCUGUGGCUCCAUAUACCUUUCGACCAUUUUCUGCUGGAAGAGGAAGAUUCACGGCCCCUGAGGAGAUCCAGAGGAAAGAGACGGUCUCCAAGGGUGCUGUGCAGCAAGGAGCCCAGGAGUGGUAUGAACCGUAACAGUGCCCUUAGAGUAAAUGUGCGGCCCCUAAGACCCUGCCCUCAGGAAGGCGGCCUUCCCCUGCAGUCCUGUGUCCCACCCCUGGGUCUCUGUAGGGUGCCAUCCAGGGCAAGCAACCCAAGCACUGCUUCCCACCGGGUGAUGAGCCAUGCAGGCCUCCAAACUGCACGUCAUGAUUCAUCCCUAAAGUGAGUUUGGCCUUGAGAGUCCCCAGGGUCCUCCCCCACUGGGCAGGGGUCCUCAAAGCCAAGGAAGCCUGGUGACACAGGCACCCAUGGGAGGUGGGCCCAGAAAGGGGCUUCCCAUAGAUAGGCCCUGUGAGUAGGGAGCUUGUACACUGGGCCAUGGGCAGCGCCAGUUCCCUUGAGCAGUAAAGGCCCUUUUCCCCCUACGGUGGGACCCAGGAGUCUCUCUGACAGCUUUUCUGCCAGGCACAGUGGCUCAUGCCUGUAAUCCCAACACUCUGGGAGGCCGAGGCGGGAAGAUCACUUGAGGUCAGGAGUUCAAGACCAGCCUGGCCAACAUGGUGAAACGUCGUCUCUGCUAAAAAUACAAAAAUUAGCUGGGUGUGGUGACAGGCGCCUAUAACCCCAGCUAUUUGGGAGGCUGAGGCAGUAGAAUCGCUUGAACCCAGAUAGCAGAGGUUGCAGUGAGCUGAGAGUGUGCCAUUGCAGAGAGACUCCAUCCCAAAAAAAGACAGCUGUCCCAGGCCAAGGGUACUUGGGAGAGCCCCUCAUGGAGAACCUAGUUUAGACCAAGUAGCAGAAGCUGUGGUCAUAACAAAACAAUUUGAGGAAGAAAUCUUACAAAUCACCACUGCCCUUUCUCCUUUUCCAUAAAACUGUCCAUCUUUUCGGUGCUCCCUAAUCCAAGCAGCUUGACUUUAGAGAAGUUGCAGAAGCAGUGAAGCCACUAACAUGCUGUGUGACUUUAUGCAAGUCACUCACCUCACUGAGCCACCUCCAUUUCUUCAUCUGUGAAAUAGGCAUAACAGUAAUACAUAACCCUACCUACCUCACAGGGCUGUUGUGAGGAUCAAAUGAAAUAAUGUAACGUGAGAAUACAGUAUAAAUGAUAAAGGA